GAGCAACUUCCAGUCCUGCAAGCUCCAUUCAUGCAGCCAUCCUGCUAUAUAGACUGGCUGUGCAGCCGCAGGCCCCAUCACACUGAACUCGCAUCAUCCGUGUCAACCAGCCAUGGGGAAGAUCACCUUCUAUGAGGACAGGGCCUUCCAGGGCCGCAGCUACGAAACCACCACUGACUGCCCCAACCUGCAGCCGUAUUUCAGCCGCUGCAACUCCAUCCGGGUGGAGAGCGGCUGCUGGAUGCUCUAUGAGCGUCCCAACUACCAAGGUCAACAAUACUUGCUGCGGCGAGGGGAGUACCCCGACUACCAGCAAUGGAUGGGCCUCAGCGACUCCAUCCGCUCCUGUUGUCUCAUCCCCCAAACAGUCUCCCACAGGCUGCGGCUGUACGAGAGGGAAGACCACAAAGGCCUCAUGAUGGAGCUGAGUGAAGACUGCCCCAGCAUCCAGGACCGCUUCCACCUCAGCGAGAUCCGUUCCCUCCACGUGCUGGAGGGCUGCUGGGUCCUCUACGAGCUGCCCAACUACCGGGGGCGGCAAUACCUGCUGAGGCCCCAAGAGUACAGGCGGUGCCAGGACUGGGGGGCCAUGGAUGCUAAGGCAGGCUCUUUGCGGAGAGUGGUGGAUUUGUAUUAAAAUAGCUUAACACUACCAAUUUCCCAUUUUGGAACCUAAUAAAUAUUUAGUCUGCAUUGCUGGCAA